GUUACCAUAGCGACGUGCACGCAGUAGCCAGGCCUGACCCGCUGGUCCCUUGCUGGCGGGAGGAAAGAGGCGGCACCAUGAGCCACGCAGUAACCAUCGAGGAGCCCCAGGCCCAGCCGCAGGUGUCUCAAACUCGGUACCGGGAGAGGUCGCGGGCUGGGAGCCACAUCUCCUCCAAUCGAGCGUAUGAUUUUCUGUACGGUAAGGACCGCCGCAGACCUUCCUCCGCGUCCGUCGCCUCCUAGGCCAGAUCCAUUGUUUAUUGUGUCAAGUGAGAAAGACCAUACACAGGCAAAUAUCCAAGCUACCCUGAUUCGCAGCAGACUGAGAAAAGUUCCCAGGUUUAAAACCAUGUUCAGUAACCUGAUCCAUUAUCCAAGAUAUUCUCUAUAUUGGAGCAAGUCAGAUCCUGUCCCACCAUUUAUCAGUCGGGAAUGGAAGGGACAUAAGGAGAAACACAGAGAAGCCCUCCGGCAGCUCACCACAACUGACGCUUCUUUUCAGAUGCCUAAAGAAGUUUAUGAAGAUCCUGAAGUUACUGGAAAGAAUCGCUAUAAAUACUUUGAAAGGCCUUUUCUCCCAUUUUUUCAGCAGAUGCCAUUCAAUGUUGUUUAUGCCGUAUCCAAGGCAGAACCAUACACUUUUCCUCCUACUUCUACUAAGCACCUAUCCAUCCCUUCAAAGUCUACUGUGGGCACUCAGACUGAUUAUCGGGAUGCUGACGUUCAAACAGAUCCAUACUCUGCAGAAUAUGUAGUAUGUCAGGACUCAAUCCCUGAGCUCUUGACCCUGGCUACGCUUACUUGGGGUCGGGGUCUCCCAGCAGGACAAGCUGAGGUGGAGAUGAUAGAAAGAGCCCGCGAGAAGCGUGCUUGGGAAGCCUCUCUCCCCGCUCUGAGUGACACCUCCCAGUUUGAGAAGAGGAGGAAAAUGAUGAAUGAAAUGGAGAGGAAGGAGUGGGCCUUCAGAGAGCAGGAGAUUGAAAAACUGCAGGAGAUUCGCCUGGAAGUUCUAAAAGAGCUGUUGAGGAAGCGUGAAGAGAAUCAGAAUGAAGUGAAUAUGAAGCACUUGAAUGCCCGGUGGUCUAAACUGCAGGAGGGAAAAGAGGCAAAAAUGGCAAAAAUUCAGCGCACGCAUGUAUCAACAAUCAGAAAACUUGUAGGAAAGAGAAAGAAUAUAGAAGGGAAGUUGGAGAGAAGAAAUAUCAUCAAGGAUUAUUCUGAUUAUGCAUCACAGGUCUAUGGACCUCUGUCUCGUCUUGGGUGUUUCCCAGACAACAACUCAGAGGACUUUGUAGUAAAAAACUACUAUCUCAACACCUAUGAAGGAUUAGUGGAACUUGAGUCAUGUCUCCCAGAUUUUGUGACACAACCCCAAAUCAGAGCUCCAAAACCUAAAGUCAUUACCACCAAAGCUGGUUUUCUGAAGAGGGCAGCAAGGUUGGACUAUGAGUUGGCAGAGGUUCAUAAGGCACUGUUGGAUAAGAAGAAUAAAGUUCUUGAAGUAAAGAAACCCCCUCGCUUCCUUCAAAGAAACCCAAUACCUCAACCUCGGCUUCCAACUCCAACCUUGGAAAUGACGUCCAAUGAAGAAGAAGAAAUGGAAAUGGCUGUGAUCUACCUUCAAAAGUUACUCCGGGGCAGAGUCGUUCAGAACAUGAUGUUUGAAGGGAAAGAAAAGCGACUGGAGUUGAUCCAGGAGUUGCGCACCUGCCACGCACUACAAGAAGAUGAAAAGCUGGUGAAAAAAGCCGAGAAGCAAGUGACCCUGGCCUUACAGCGGCAGAGGAACUUGCAUGAGCACAAGGUGUCACUGGUUGAAAACCAUUUGGCCGGACUGGAAGGAAGGGCACUAGCAGACAUGUUUGACUUCCUGUCCAAAGAGCUGGUGAGACUGCAGGAGGAGAGGAGGAUCCAUGCCUUUGUCAUGCUGGCUGAGCGCCAGCGGCGGGUACGAGAGGCUGAAGAGAGUGGUCGGCGCCAGGUGGAAAAACAGCGCCUGCGGGAGGAGGACGAGAUAUUUAAGGAGGUGGUUAAAGUUCACCAUAGUACUAUAAGCUCCUACCUAGAAGACAUAAUACUGAAUACCGAAGCGAAUACUGCAGAAGAACAAGCCAGGGCAGAAAUAGAGAAGAUGGCUGAGAAAAUCAAUGACAUUGCUUAUGAAAUGGAAAGCCGCCGAACCUAUCUUCAGUCAGAGGAGAUUGUUGCUGAGUUGGUUUAUAGUUUUCUGAUCCCAGAGGUGCAAAAAUACUUUGUCAAAGAAAAAGUGAGGAACGCACAGCGGAAACAUAUUCUUGCAGCCCAUCAGAUCAUCCACAGUUACACGGAAAGCAUGGUUCAAAAGAAAUUAACUGAGGGAGAGCAAGAUGAGGCCUCAAAUGCUGCCAUGUUACUUGAGAAAGAAACUCAAAAUGAGAACAACAGCUAAGAUUGUGAUUUUUUUGUAAAAGAAGCUGUACGAAUCAUCAUAAAUAAUUCCAAUAGUCUGCACUUCUCCCAAGGUGUGCACUGCUCAUAAACUUGCCAGUGUGUGAUUCAUGAGAAAGGAGAUUUAUUUUCCUUAAACAUCCAAUAAUUUAAAAUGAUUUUCAAUAAUAAUAAUCAAAUGAAAAAGCUUCAUUCUCUUCAGUGUCUUCUAGAUGCCCUACUUAAAGAGAACAUUUUCUUAUGUCUCAUUUCAAUAUUUUGUUAACUAUGAGGAUGUGCUGGUUUGUUGAAUCAAACAAAAGGAAAUGUUGUGGAAUAUUUUUCCAAGUAGUUUUGGUUCACUAUUCACAGGACAUUGGCAUUAUCUACUAAGGCUGAAAAUGUGCAUAUUCCAUGACUCAGGAUUUUAUCUCCUAGAUAUAUAUUCAACAGAAAUGCAUGAGUAUGUGCACCAACAGGCAUGACAAAAAUAUUUAUAGUAGUGGUGUUCACAAUAGUCCCAAACUGGAAACCCAAGUGUCCAUCUCCAUCGGAACAGAAAACUAUACUUUGGUCUGCUUCUACAGUGGCACAUCAACCCACCUUUGAGCUUUAGAUCUAAGAAGUGUGUUCAUGCAACAGCCAUAGAGAUGGUGCUAUUGAAAGGCAAUCUGCCCAUCCUGUGUAUUGACAAGCAUCAGGAUUCCAGGAGGAUUCUUCCUGAUUCAAAGACUGUCAAAUAGGAAAAAAGAAAACAGUAAAUGAACAAAAACAUCAACAUGGAGUCCAAGUAAUGAAUUUAUAGAGGAAAAUGUAUGCUACUCUGAAAACAAAGCUUAUGUUAGAGAAUAUCUUACUGUAAGAAACAAGGAAAAUUGCAGAAACAUUUGCUGAGUGUUUUUAAUAGGAGUCAAAAAGAAAGGGUCUUUUCAGAAACUGAAGUAGGAAAUAAUAACAGACAAGGUCAAAAAAUAGAUGCAGGCUGAAAAGAAAAGGAAGUGGGCUAAGAUGGGAAAAAUAUAAAAAGAUUUAAAAUCCAGCAACAAAAUUUACACAUUCAUUUGGAUGCAGUGAAAAGGGCAGAAAUACCACAGCAGAGAAUAAAAUUGAUAAUGUUGGCAACACAUUUAUUAAGUGAUCCAACAUGGGAUGGGAAGGAAUGGGCAAAGAGAUUAAAAUGACAGAAGUUAGCUGUAGAUGACCUAUCCCACAGCAAUCGGAGUUCUUGAAGAAGAAACCAGAACAAAUAAAAUAGAAACAAUAAUCAGAGUUUAAUAAUUAAUUUUCUGAGUUUUUUUUUAAAAAAACUAAUUAUACAAACUUGAAAGGGUUCACCUUGCCCUAGCAAAACUAGGAUUGGGACACCUUUUUUUCCCCCUGAGGAUCACUGACAAAAAACACUGCACCAGUAAGGAAGCAACUAAAUUUUGUUUUGUUCUUUGAAAAAGGCUAACCUGAGCUAGGUAAAGGUUAUAUCAUUCACUUUUGAAAUAAACCAUCGAGAACACAAAAUGACAAGUGAGUUAGGUUGGGCUGAUGGGAUAGAAGGUGGGAGGGGAAUGCUAUACAGCUGGGAACAGCAGACUUUCUCUGAAGGGCCAGAUGGUAACUACAUUAGGGUUUGCGGGUCUGAUGGUCGCCAUCAUAACUGCAUACUCAACUCUGCCGUUGUAGGGUAAGAGCAGCACUCGAUGACACAGAAAUGAAUGCACAUGACUGUGUUCCAGUAAAAUUUUAUUUUAAUUAAAAUCAAUUCAUGUUUGAAAAAGGAUUUAAAGUAGCUUCUAAUAAAGGACAUGUGUAAUGAAACUUAAAAUAUGAUAUUUUCUUUAAAAAUCUUUAUCCUUAUGUAGACUUCUAAAACUAUGUUUUGCAUUUAGACAGUCAAGGAAAAUACAAGUUGUUAUACAAUUCUCAUUGACUAAUUGAAGUUUACUAGGAGAGGAAAACUUUUUCUUGAUACCGGCAAUCUUUUACUUAUAAUGGCUUGAGUUAAAAUGCUCCAACUUUUCUAAUUUUUGCUUUUGAAAAUAAAACACCUAUAGUGACAAUAAAAACACACAUUUAAAGCCAA